GUUGGAGAUGUGUGAGCGCAGUCUCUACAGAGCGGGCUAUGUGGGCUCGCUUCUGAAUCUGCAGUCGCCAGACUCUUUCUACUUCUCCAACCUGAGGCCGAAUGGCGGCCAGUUGGCCGCGCUUCCCCCUAUCUCCUACCCGCGCGGCGCGCUGCCCUGGGCCGCCACGCCCGCCUCCUGCGCCCCCGCGCAGCCUGCGGGCGCCACUGCCUUCGGCGGCUUCUCGCAGCCCUACCUGGCUGGCUCCGGGCCUCUCGGCCUGCAGCCCCCAACAGCCAAAGACGGACCCGAAGAGCAGGCUAAGUUCUAUGCGCCCGAAGCGGCCGCUGGGCCAGAGGAGCGCGGUCGUACCCGGCCGUCCUUCGCCCCCGAGUCUAGCCUGGCUCCUGCAGUGGCUGCUCUCAAAGCGGCCAAGUAUGACUACGCUGGUGUGGGUCGUGCCACGCCGGGCUCCACGACCCUGCUCCAGGGGGCUCCCUGCGCCCCUGGCUUCAAGGACGACACCAAGGGCCCGCUCAACUUGAACAUGACAGUGCAGGCGGCGGGCGUUGCCUCUUGCCUGCGACCUUCACUGCCCGACGGCCUGCCGUGGGGGGCGGCCCCGGGGAGGGCCCGCAAGAAGCGGAAACCCUACACGAAGCAGCAGAUUGCGGAGUUGGAGAACGAAUUCCUCGUCAACGAAUUCAUCAACAGGCAGAAACGCAAGGAAUUGUCCAAUAGGCUGAACCUCAGCGACCAGCAAGUCAAAAUCUGGUUCCAGAACAGGCGUAUGAAGAAGAAGCGCGUGGUGCUUCGGGAGCAGGCGCUGGCGCUCUACUAGCCGCGCGCGUGGCCAGGGCCGGGUUGGAUCUGCCCUUUUGGACAGAGGCCUUGUUUGGGGAGGGGGAUCUGGGGCUAAGGCUAAGGCUUUUCCUUCGGUUCCUUCUCUGCUGGCCCCAGAAGCCACCAAGAGAUUUACAGACCAGGCCAGUUGGGCCUCCUUGCUUUCCUCAGUCCCUGAGAAGCCCGUGAGAAACGUGCGGAAGUACCAGUGCAACUCUGGCUGGCCUUAAGGCUUCCACGUUGGGGGACUGAGGCCAACUCUCCUUGCUCCUGGCUGGGGCAUUUGCACCCACCGCUCAUUCUUGCUCCCCGGUACCUGGAUUUUUCUGUUUCCACCCAAUUCGUUCUCCCUUUCCCCCUCUCUCCAGCCCCUUCAGCGUAUAGCAGUCGCCUAGUUAGGGCUCAGAGUGGAAGGCCUCCUGAGGGAAUGGAAAGGACUGUGGGUACAAUUAGGUCUCUGCAGCAGAAGCCCUUUGUGGCAAGGCCAGGAUCUUCACUCUGGAGAAAGGAAAGGGCACCAUCCACCCUCCACCCUCCUGUCUGCCCUGGCUGAUUUGAGAGAACAAAAGCCACACUAGAUCUUCAGACUUUGGGAGGAAAAGGGAGGGAAGGGGAGGGGCUGGGUAGUGGGGUAAACUUGGAGAUAUCUCGAAAUGAGAAAUGCGAAAUAGGCUGGCCUAUUUCCAGCUGGGUAGAAUAUGUGGAACCUUCAUUUCCUGAGAUGGGAUGAGAGAGACUGGGACUCCAGACAAGUGCCAUCUCCAGACAAGACUGGCAAACAUUGCCCUACUCCCACCUUCUCAAACAUGCCUAGGCCAGGCCUAUGAACCCUGUAACUGGAUCCCCAGAGGCUAGCUCUGGUGAAAGGAGCUGUUGGUCUGCUUUGAAGCUCUGUUGCACAGGGAGAGGGAAAAAUAUCCAGGGGAGGAGAAGGGAGUGAAUAAGAGGAGGAGGGGUGCUGCACUCCAACUGUAAAUAUGGCUUUCCAGUUGAGGUGAGUAAAGGUGUUGGUGCAUCUUUCUUUCUUCAAUUACCUUAAUGGAACCCCAUAAGGAUAGGCAAAAAUCCUUCUCAAGAGUCAAGGGGAGGGGAAGGAAGUCUCUUAGAUUCUCUGCCCCGCUAGCUGCUCUUGACAAAGCAAAGAGGACCAGAAGUUCCUCUCACCGUCUCUACCAUCUGCCAACUCUACCAGAGGCCCAGCUACUGUGCCCCUUCUGAGGCAUGUCUGGCCUGUCCCAGUGGAGACUUUAAGGCCCUGGGCCCUGCCAGGCUUGCCUCAUGGAGGCAGGGGUUCCCAAAUGCCAGGUGGAGUUGUUCUGGGUGUACUGGAGUGUCCCGCCUUAAUCUCAGUGAACCAAGCCUCCCCCUGCGAGCUCAUUCCACUAUCCCUGCCUCUUCUCCCCUCUCCUUCUGACAUGUAGCACUCCUCCUUCGCAAUUCCUAGCAUGAUGCACAACAACUCAAGGAUUCAGGAUUCCUUCCCAAAGUCCAGUGAUUUCUUUUCAGUGCAGGACCUGGCCCUAAAUCUGGAGUGGGCCCCUCACAGAGAGCCCUGAGCCUUAGCCCAACUGACUUCAGUUGAUAUUUAAACUAAUUUCAUUUUCUAGGCUAUCUAAUAGUUAUCAUGCAUGUUUUGUUUUGAUUUUGUCAAAAACAGUAGCUUGUAUAUAUCAGACACAAUAUAUACAAAUGUUUUGAGUGAAAAUAAAUAUCCAGGUCUGAGCCAA